AGGAGGAGCUCGCUGUUACCUGAAGGGAUGGACUGGUCGGUGGAAUGUCCGGUGCCGUGAGUUACCUGCUCAGCCCUGGAGCAGGGGUCAAAGCUGGGCGGAGCUGGACAGCCAGUCUCAGCCUCAGGUACUCCAGUGACAAGCAGCAGCACCAGUGCUGAUGAGGGUAGCAGGGAAAACUGGUGAAAUGUGCCGAGGUCUCUCCAGAGGUGGUAGGCGGUUGCGCCAGCUUCACAUCCUGGAUAGGCAGGAACGUUUCCCUAUCAUACUCCUGUCCCGGGUCUCAUGUGUCUCAGUUCAAACAGACACUGCCGUCUAUCUUCAAGCUGCAAUGAAGCUGAGAGCCACAGAAAACACCUGUACCAUGGUUUCAGGGAGGAGUCUCUUCCCUCAGCCGAAAACAGACAGCUUUGCUGGUCAUCUGUUCUCCACUGCGAGGACGCUGCCACUCAGUGUGGAGAGAGGAAGGGGUUCUGCCUAUGGUGCAAGAAGGUCGGACUCGGCAGAAAUUGCAACAGCCAGUUCAACCUUCAGCAACCACCAUACUGAUCAGUAGUCAUCAACAUUGAGACGAGACUGUACACCAGCAAAAAGAUCCCAACUCAAUGAAGGCUCAGAUGAUUUUAGCAUUUUUUUAGCAAUAAAGCAUUUUUAAAUUAAACUAUAUACAUUGUUGUUUUAGACAAGUUUUUGCACAUUCAGAAUACAGUAAAGUGUAAACAUGACUUUUAUAUACACUGGGGAAACCAAAAAAUUUGUGUGACUUACUUUAUUGCAAUAUUUGUUUUAUUGUGCUGAUCUGGAGCUAAAUAUAUCUGAGAUAUGCUUGUACUGAUGAUUAUUUUAACACCAAGAUAUUUUAAAAUUCAUUAAAUAAAUGUUUAUUUAAAUAGA